ACAGCAGCUCUACCCCUCACGACGCAGACAUGGCAGCGCAGAAGGACCAGCAGAAAGAUGCCGAGGCGGAAGGGCUGAGCGGCACGACCCUGCUGCCGAAGCUGAUUCCCUCCGGUGCAGGCCGGGAGUGGCUGGAGCGGCGCCGCGCGACCAUCCGGCCCUGGAGCACCUUCGUGGACCAGCAGCGCUUCUCACGGCCCCGCAACCUGGGAGAGCUGUGCCAGCGCCUCGUACGCAACGUGGAGUACUACCAGAGCAACUAUGUGUUCGUGUUCCUGGGCCUCAUCCUGUACUGUGUGGUGACGUCCCCUAUGUUGCUGGUGGCUCUGGCUGUCUUUUUCGGCGCCUGUUACAUUCUCUAUCUGCGCACCUUGGAGUCCAAGCUUGUGCUCUUUGGCCGAGAGGUGAGCCCAGCGCAUCAGUAUGCUCUGGCUGGAGGCAUCUCCUUCCCCUUCUUCUGGCUGGCUGGUGCGGGCUCGGCCGUCUUCUGGGUGCUGGGAGCCACCCUGGUGGUCAUCGGCUCCCACGCUGCCUUCCACCAGAUUGAGGCUGUGGACGGGGAGGAGCUGCAGAUGGAACCCGUGUGAGGUGUCUUCUGGGACCUGCCGGCCUCCCGGGCCAGCUGCCCCACCCCUGCCCAUGCCUGUCCUGCACGGCUCUGCUGCUCGGGCCCACAGCGCCGUCCCAUCACAAGCCCGGGGAGGGAUCCCGCCUUUGAAAAUAAAGCUGUUAUGGGUGUCAUUCAGGAAA